GUCCCUGGAGCCUGGGAAGACGGUGGGUGACCAGAGAGUCCUGUCUAUCCUAGGAGGAGAACAUUCAGCCCAAAUCCCAGCCCCAUCAUGCACAGAUCAGAGCCAUUUCUGAAAAUGUCGCUGCUGAUUCUGCUUUUCCUGGGAUUGGCAGAAGCCUGUACUCCUCGUGAAGGUAAUGCUUCCAGCCAUGCCUUGUGUCCUCUAUGUAUUUUCUUACAACUUGGGAGGCUCUUGUGGGCUGGAUUCAGAGAGAAGCUCCUGAAGUCUAACAGACUUCUUCUUGCUUCCCAUUUAGACAUUCACAUUUCCCUUGAUGGACACAGUGGGGUGAAUGAGUCUAGGUUGCUAGCCCCUGCCCUUGGAGAUACACUUGUGUCUGCAUCCUGGUUUCUAUCACUGAUUCUGUGACUUUGGGGAGACACUGCGUCUGCAAACCUUGCUGUCCUCAUCUGACCAACGGGGCUCACAAGAAUCCCCAGUUCAUGGGACUGUUGCAUGUCAUUGACGAGCUUACGUUGUGCAGUGCCUGGAAGUCAACAUUACCAUAGUUAGAUAAUUCUAGUGAGACUCCAGACUUUUGCGACGUAAAGACACCAAAGAGUAUAUUGGGAAGAGGACUUGGGUCUUGCCAUAACUCUGAGUUCCCAUUUCCUCAUUCGAUCCACAAAUGUUUAUUCCUGGUUCUUUCCACGGGCUUGAUGCUGGGAAUAUAGUGAUGAAAAUAGUUCUGUCUUCAUGGAAUUCUCAUGCUAAACACACACAUUCUAGUGUGGGGAUUCGGAGAUGGCCUCUCUAGAAAAGUCACAUUUGAGGUAAGGAAUAGGAGCUGGCCAGCUGAAGAGUUAGGAGAGACUAUUCCAGGCAGAGACUUGAAUAUGCAAAGGUCCUGGGGCAGAAGGCACUGAGUCCCUCCAUCAGAGAGAGGCCGGUGUGUCAGGAACGUGGUAGGCAGAAGGAGGGGCAUGGUGGUGAGACUGUUACAAGUAAGAAGAGACAGGAGGCAGGAAACAGAACAGACGGGGGCAUGUGAGUCACAGGAAAAAUGUUGGAUGUUAUCCUCAGGGAAAAGGAAGCUGUGAAAGGGUUUUCAGCAAAGGAGUGUCAUAUUUAGGAGCGUGUGUGUGCAUGUAUGUGUGUUUCUGUGUGUUUAAACAAUGUGUCUUGCCCUCAGGAAAGAAUGGAUUAGGUGGGAAUCAGAUUAGGGGCAAACACACAAGUUAGAAAACGUUUUGGUCAUCAGGGUGAAGAUGGGGAUAAGUAGAAGGUUACGAGGCACUGAGGAAACAGCUCACAGGAUUGAGUGAUGGGUCAGAUGCUGGUGGUUGGGGAUAGAGAAGCAUGCAGAAAGGCUCUCUUUAUACAUACAUGUAUUUGCAACUGGGGAAUUGAGGCUGCCCUUAACUGAGAUGAGAAAACUCUGUAGAGGUCGGGCGCGGUGGCUCACACCUGUAAUCCCAGCACUUUGGGAAGCCAAGGCAGCUGGAUUAUUUGAGGUCAGAAGCUCAAGACCAGCCUGGCCAACAUGGCGAAACCCCAUCUCUACUAAAAAUACAAAAAUUAUCCAGGCAUGGUAGUAGGGGCCUGUAAUCCCAGCUACUCAGGAAGCUGAGGCAGGAAAAUCGCUUGAACUCAGGAGGUGGAGGUUGCAGUGAGCCGAGAUCCUGCCAUUGCACUCCAGCCUGGGAAACAGAGCAAGACUCUGUUUCAAAAAGAAAAAAAGAAAAAAAAAAAAACUCUGUAGAGGAACACGUUUUUUAAAAAAUUUAUUUUGAAAUUAUUUUAGACUUGAGGAAAAGUCACAAAAAUUAAGUUUCUGAAUAUUCUUCACCCAGUUAUCUCAGCUGUUAACAUCUUACCUAACCAUAGCACAAUGACUAAAAGCAAGACCCAACACCAGAACAAAACUAUUAAAGAAAUUACAGACCUCAUUCAAAUUUUACUAAUGUUUCUACUAAUAGAAAAACUAUUCUAUUUGAGGAUCCAAUCCAGGAUCCCACCUUGUAUUUUCAAUUAAGUUUUUUGUUUUGUUUUGUUUUGUUUUGUUUCAGAAAAUCCAGCUCUUGCUCAACCAUGUUGCAUUUUGUUAUCCCAUCUCCUUUGGUCUUGUGAUUUGUCCUUAGGAUGUGUGAUUGAACCUCCUCAAUCUUUGUCUUUCACGACCCUGAAACAUUUGAAGAGCUCUGAUCAGUUGUUUUGCAGAAUUUCUCUCAAUUUGGGUUUGUCUGAAGCUUUCUCAUGAUUGGAUUGAGACUAUGCAUUUAGGGCAGGAAUACCACAGAAGUGGUCUCACACCCUUCCCCGGGAAUUAUAUCAGGGACCACAUGAUGUUGAUGUGUCUUAUUACCCAUGGUGUAAACUUUAGUCCCUCGGCUAAGGUGGUGUCUGCCAGGUUUCUCCACUGUUAAGUUACUAUUUUCCCCCUUUGUAAUUAAUAAAUACGCUGGGGGAGAAAUUUUGAGGCUAUGCGAAUACCCUGUUCUCCUCCAAUUUUUGCCCAUUAAUUUUAGCAUCCAUCUGUGGAUCUUGCUGCAGAAAUGAUUGCUACAGUGCUUCUCCAAUGGUGAUUUUCUAUUCCCCUUAUUCAUCUACAUAUAUUCAAUGGCCUUUCUCUGUAAGGAAAAGCUGACUUUUCUUCUCCAUUUAUUUAUUCAAGUACUGUAUUUAUUUAUAUCAGCGUGAACUCAGGGAUAUUUAUCGUAUUGGUUGGGUGCAGUGGCUCAAGCCUUUAAUCCCAGCACUUCGGGAGGCCAACGCAAGAGGAUCACUUGAGGCCAGGAGUUUGAGACCAGCCUGGGCAACAUAGUGAGACUCAUCUCUACAAAAAAUAGUAAGAAUAAAUAAAAAGUAUUGCAUUAACAGAUUAUUUUUUGAUGGAUAGGAGUGUGAUGACCACAGAUUCUUUUUUGAACAGGCUAAGCUUGAAGCACCUGUAAGAUGUUUGGGACAUCCAUAGAUAGCAAGUUCUGUGAGAACAGAGUUUGGGGUGUCUAGUGUACUCUUAUACCAGAACUUCUCUUCCCAAUCAGCCUUGCAAAUACCUACAGAGCAGGGGCUGAAUCUGAUUUAUCUGCGUCUCCAACACCAAACAUGGGCCAAUGCCCAGAGCAUGUACCAUGUGAAUGUUGGUUGGAUGGAUGAUGAACGAAUGGACUUAUCGAUGGAUGGAUGGGCUGAUAGAUGGGCCCGAGUAGCUUUAUUGAUAGCAGUGAGUGGGUCAGCUGAUCUCCAGGGACACUUCUAUCUCUGGUCUUCUUGGUUAUUGCACUGAUCUGAGUCUAAUGCUAAUUUCUCUCUCUGCUCCCUGCUCCCGUUGUGAACUGGCUGGCUGAUGCUUUUGUCUCCAGUUGCAACUAAAGAAAAAAGUAAGAACCGUGGAACCCCCAAGUCUGUAUUUUCAUAGCUACCUCUCCUAAAAUUCUUUUCGAUCUUGCAACCUCUCUGGCAAUUCUGGGGAAGGGUGGCACUUGGAUCUGGUGCACAGACCUGCCAUGGGGUCUGGACAUGACUCAGAAAAGCAAACCUAUUGUUUGCUUACAGUGAUGCUCACAACUAAAAGAGCAGCCCUCCUUCACUCCUUUGUCUGGGGAAGAGAGGCCUAUUCGGAAAAUGAAGAGCAUUUAUCAGGGAAGAGAGACUUCGGGCAGAUCUCCAUUAGAAUAACACCUUGGCUUAUGUUUAACACCAGCUGGUGGUUUGCAAACUUCAUGGUCUUAGGGCCACUGAACACGCGAAAAAAAUUAUUAAGGAUCUAAAGAGCUCUUUUUUUUUUUUUCCAGUGAGGGUUAUUUUUAUUUAUUUAUUUAUUUUUGAGACGAGCCUCGCUCUGUCGCCCAGGCUGGAGUGUAGUGGUGCGAUCUGGGUUCACUGCAACCUCUGCCUCCUGGGUUCAAGCGAUUCUCCUGCCUCAGCCUCCCGAGUAGCUGGGACUACAGGCUGCGCGCCACCAUGCCCGGCUAAUUUUGUAUUUUCAGUAUAGACGGGGUUUCACCAUGUUGGUCAGGCUGGUCUCGAACUCCUGACCUCAGGUGAUCCGCCCACCUCGGCCUCCCAAAGUGCUGGGAUUACAGGUGUGAGCCACUGUGCCCGGCCAAAGGUUAUCUUUAUUGAUAUUUACCUUAUUGUAAAUUCAAGGAUUUUUAACUUAAAAAUAUUUAUAUUUACAAAUAUUAUAAAUAUUUACAAAUACAAAUACUUAUAUUUACAAAAACUAUUUCUAUUUACAAAUAAGCACAUAAAAAGAUGCUCAACCUCAUUAGCCAUCAGAAAAAUGGAAGCCAAAGCCACAGUGAGGUAUCACUUCACACUAACUAACGUGGAGAAAUCAGAACCCUCAUAUGCUGCUGGUGGGAAUGUGAAAUGAUACAGCUGCUUUGGAAAACAGUCUGGCUGUUCCUCAAAAUGUUAAACACUGAGUUACUCAGCAAUUCCGCUCUAGGUAUGUGCCCAAGAUAAAUGAAACGUAAGUCCACACAAAAACCCAUGCACAAAUGUUCACAGCAGCACUAUUCCUAAGAGCUAGCAAGUGAAGGUAAUCCUAGCAUGCAUCCAUUAAUGAAUGGAGAAACAGAGUGUGGUCUAUGCAUACAAUGGAAUAUUAUUCACCCAUAAAAAGAAACAAAGUUCUGAUGCAUUCAACAUCGUGUGUGAGCCUUGAAAACAUUAUUCUCAGUGAAAGAUGCCAGUGAUAAAAGAUCACAUAUUACCUGAUUCCGUUUACCGUAUAUGAAAUAUUCAGGAUAGGCAAAUCCAUAGAGACACAAUGGACAUUAGUGAUUUCCAGGGGGUGAGGGGUGGGGGAAUUUAGAGACAAUGACUAAGGGGUUCAGGGUUUAUUUUGGGGUGAUUAAAGCCUCUAAAACUGGUGUAGUGAUGGUCGUACAAGUCUGAGUAUCCUACAAACCACUGAAAUGGGUGAAUUGCAUGGUAUGUGAAUUAUAUCUCAGUAAAGCUAUUAUUCAAAUAUCUAUUACUGCAUUAAAAAAAUAAGGAUAAUAGAGACUCAGAAGGAAGGAGGGUGGCAGGGAGGUGAGGGAUGAAAACUACCUUUUGGGUACAAUGUACAUUACAAAGAUGCUGGUGCACUAAAAUCCUAGACUUCACCACUGCACAAUUCAUCCAUGUCACCAAAAACCACUUGUACCCCUAAAGCUACUGAAAUUAAAAAUAUUUGAAAAAUAAGGAUAAUAAAUAUACAUACUGACAUAAAUAAAAUGUUUUAGUGAAAUGGCUGUUUCCAAACCAAAAAAGUUUAGUAAGAAAGGUAUUAUUUUACAUUUUUGCAAAUCUCUUUGAUGUCUAGUUUAAUAGAAAACAGCUGAAUUCUCAUUUCUGCUUCAGUCUGUCACAAUGUGCUAUUUUUUUUUUUUUUAGCUUUAUGUGUUUGUUUAUUUUGGAGACGUAGUCUUGCUCUGUCGCCCAGGCUGGAAUACAGUGGCACGGUCUCGGCUCGCCAUGACAUCUGCCUCCUGGGUUCAAGCAAUUAUCUUGCCUCAGCAUCCGAAGUAGCCUCCCAAGUAGCUGGGACUAUAGGUGCAUGCCACCAUGCCUGGCUAAUUUUUGUAUAUUUAGGAGAGACAAGGUUUCACCAUGUUGGCCAGGCUGGUUUUGAACUCCUGACCUCAAGUGAUCUGCCCACCUCGGUCUCCCAAAGUGCUGGGAUUACAGGCGUGAGCCGCCCCGCCCAGCCACAAUGUGCUAUUUUGGUUGAAGCAAAUGAAAAUCUAAUCUCACACAGAUAAGGAGUUGGAAAAGGGAAGAUCAUGCAGACCCGUUUUAGGCAGAGUUCUCCAGAGAGACAGAACCAUGAAGAUAUACAUAUAGAUACAUAUAUAGAUAAAGAUAUUGAUAGAGAUAUUUGAGAACAAAUUUCUUAGGGGAAUUAGCUCACUCAGUUGUGGGGUCUGCAAGCUGCAGAACCAGGAGGGCCAGUAGUGUGGCUCAGUCCAAGUCUGAAGGCCUCAGAACCAAGGAAGCUGAUGGAUGGUCUAACUAACUCUCAGUCUGAGGCCAAUGGCCUGGGAGCUCAGGGAGCUGUUGGUUCAAGUCCUAGAAUCCCAAAAGCUGGAGUACCUGGAGUUCUGACAUCCAAAGCCAGGAGAAGGGCAUCCCAGCUGCAGAAGGGAGAGCAAGAAUUGACCCUUACUCCACCUCUUGGCUUCAGCUGGGCCUCCAUCCAACUGGAUGGUGCUCACCCACCGUGAGGGUGGAUCUUCCCUACCUAGUCUUCCAACUCACACCCCAAUAUCCUCCAGAAACACCUUCACAGACACACCUGGGGCAGCCCAAACAUUCUAAUCAAAUGCCAAACCACUCAGGCUUCCCUUUCAGCAGAAGACGGAUGGACUCAGUGCCUACUGAAGCAUUGAGAAUAAACGUCUUACUGCUAUAUGGGUGCCUUAGUCAAGCUGACACCCCAAAUCAACCAUCACAUCCCCUGAAAGGAUCUCAGGGACCACCUCCCACCCCCACCAAGUAGUCUUUGGAUGAUACUUCGAGAAUUUCUGCUCCAAGUCACAUGGAAGGGAAAAAGAUCUCUUUUUUUUCCACCCCUACUAGACUGCAAGACUGUAAGUUCCUAGAGGGCAGGGACUGUACUUUACUCAAUCUGUUUAUUCCUAUAGCCUAGCAAAAUUCCUAGCGCUCAGUAGGACUAAAUAAAUGGAAAGAGCCUUGCAAAAUGGAAAGGACUGUGAGAACAUAAUUUAAUGCUAUUAUUUCAGGUUGAAAGGAGAUAAAAGGAUCCAAUAUUAAUUAAGCAUUUAGCAUGUACUGAGAAUUUAAAAUACGUCAUGCAAUUUAAUUUUCAAAAUCGUAAGUGUCCCAUAUGGGGUCUGAGGUUUCCAAAGCUCUGAAUCCUCACACUGGACCAUCAUCAUGAGAAUCACAUGGGAAACUUUAAAAAUAUUUAAUCCCCACACCAGACUUGGUGAGCUAAAAUGCCUGCAGAUAACAUUUUGGGUUUUUUAUACCUAAAAAGCUAGCCUAUGUUAGUUCCUUCCUAUCUUCAAAAGCUGAACCUUCUAAACCUAAACAAAUGCAAACAUCUCAUGAUCCACACUGUUUUUGUUUCAAUUUAAAAUAUUAUGCUGUUUUAAUUAAAAUGUUUUAUGUUAAAUUAUUUUAUUAAUAUUUCAAUUAACAAAACAGUAUUUACAUAAACUUUAAUUACAUUUAAAUUACUAAUUAAUUAUUCAAUUUAAAACAUCAUGUUAUUUUCAUUUAAAAUAAGAUUUCCAGGGUUCAGAAUUAAAGAAGUUCUCAAGGUUAUACUGGAAAAAACUCCUUCCCAACCUAUUCACUCAUUUCCCUUCCCCGAAAGAAUCUGAUAUUAAUUAUUUCUUCCAGAUCCUUCCAGAGAUAUUUUAUGCAAGUAGAAACAAAUGUGUAUUUAUAUAUUCAAAGUCCUCUUGUUUCUAUUUUUACAAAAAAGACAGCGUAUUAUACACACUGUUCUGUAUGCACCUUACUUUUUUCACCUAAUAAUACUUCCAGAAGAUGACUCUGUGUCAGUUCAUAAGGAGCAUCCUCAACCUCUUAUUUAUACGUUUUUGGCUGAAUAAUAUUUCUUGUAUGGAAGUCCACAAUUUGUUUGACCAGUCACAUACUAAUGGCCACUCAGGUUGUUUUCAGUAGUUUGCUCUUUUAAAUAAUCCUUCAAAGAAAAAUUCAGCUUACAUGAAAUUAGACAUAUAGGAUAUAUAUCAAUGUAGAUCUACAUAUUUAUAUCUGUAGGAUUAUACAUGGAAAUAUGUAGAAUUAUAUCUAUAUAUAGAUAUAUAUUUCUUUAUCAUCUAGAUAUAACCACUGUCGUAGUCUGUUUUGGGCUGCCAUAACAGAAUACCUGAGACUGGAUAAUUUAUAAUGAAUAGAAAUUUAUUGGCUCAUGUUUCUGGAGGCUGAGAAGUCCAAGAUUGAGGGGUUGGCAUCUUGUGAGAGCCUUCCUGUUGUGUCAUCCUAUGAUCAAAGGACAGAGAGAGAGACAGAAACAGAGACAGAGAGCUCAGAGCUUCAAGCCCUUUUAUAACCAGCAUUUAUCUAUUCAUGAAAGUUGAGCCCUUGUGACCUAAAUACCUCCCAUUAGGCCCCACCUCCCAACACUGCUGCAUUUGGGAUUAAGUUUCCAACACAUGCUGUUUGGGGUACACACUCAAACCAUAACACAUACACAUUUGACCCUUGAACAAUGUGAGAGUUAGGGGCACCAACCUCCAGUGCAGUUGAAAAUUCACAUAUAACUUUUGACUUCCCCAAAACUUAACUACGAAUAGCCUACUGUUGACCAGAAGACUUACUAAUAACAUAAACAGUAGAUUAACAUAUAUUUUGUAUGUUACAUAUAUUACAUGCUGAUUCUUACAAUAAGGGAAGCUAGAGAAAAGAAAAUGUUAUUAAGAAAGAGAAAAUAUGUUUACUCUUCAUUAAGUGGAAGUGGAUCAUUAUCAAGGUCUUCAUCCUUGUCAUCUUCACAAUGAGUAGGCUGACCAGAAGAAGGAAGGGGAGGGGUUGGUCUUUCUGUCUCAGGGGUGGCAGAGGCAGAAGAAAAUGCACAUCUAAGUGGAUAAGUGUAACCAUGUAGUUCAAACCUGUAUUGUUCAAGGGUCAACGGUGUGUGUAUGUACACAUAUACAUUUACAUAUUUAUAUAAAUAUAUAUCUGUAAGAUUAAUUUCUGAAACUGCAAAGUUAAAGAAGGGUUUCUAACACUCGUGCCACUACAAUGCUAUCGCUGUAUUGAUCUUUGUCAAAUUUAUGUGACAAACUACAUAAAAAUAGCGUCCCAUAUAAAGAUCGCACUCCAUAUAACAACAGGCAAAUAAAUGUUCCAUGAAGGAAUAAAGAAAUGCAUGUAAAAAUUAACAGAGAUGGAUGAUGUUAAUAUUAAUUCCACUCUCUUCCUUGAAUUUUCCAUGUUGAUUCACUGGCUCCUGGCUCUGCUGCCCCUUCCAGUCAACUGUAAGUCAUAUCUCCUUCUCCCUACAUAAAUGGGGAGCCCGCCCUUCAACCUAGAGAAGGAAGGGAAUGAAAGAGAGAGGCAAAACUGCUGACGAUCACAUUCAACCUGGGGCAGAUUCAGAUGUCCUCAAUUCAAACAUGACCUCUUCACCCAGAAUCUGCAGAUUGCCCGGGGUGGGAACGGUGCAACUGGAUGGACUUUGAGGAGGCCAACAAGCCUCUGUCAUUAGGUCUAAAACUGGGUGUGCUGUCAGAGAGAAAGAGAACCUGUGUGGUGUUCUGGGAAAUAGCUUUGAUCAGAUUUUCAGUAGGAUCAAUGACCUACCACAAUCUAGGGGCCUUUGCUCUAGAAUGUACACCUGGGUUAGAUUGUGUGUAUUUAUUGGUGGGUUUUAGAUGAGAAAAAUAUGGUACAGGGUGGGUAAGACGUCUUCCUUUCCCAGAAUUAACAUCCAGUCUCCGGUUGAGAAGUGGAGAUGACACUUGGUUAUUAUGGAGACCUUCCUUAUGCUAGAAAUUCAGCUGGAGAAGGGAGGGUCUGGAUUCCCCAGGCCACUGGUACCCCUGAAGUUUCUGACUUCAGGGUAAAUGUGCCUCCAAAGGGGUCCAAUGCACUUAGAAUGAAUUGCAGCUCCCCAUUCUGGUUCCCUAACCUAUCUCAGGACCUAUGGGGUGCAAUGAGGUACCAAGGAUGACUUAAUUCCUUUCAUAUUCUCUCUGAACCUUCAUUGGCAAUAUGGUUCCCACUGGCUACCAUCGGUCCUGUCCUUCCUGCUGCUUGUCUGCCAACAGUGCUGAAAGGUAAGCUUCUCAUUCCAUCUCUUUCCCUUUGGGGUCUGUUUGCCUUUGUCCAAAAGGGAUCAUUGCUGCUGAACUUCGACUUACGUUUCUUCUCUGGUCUGUUCACAGCUUAGCUUCUAAUAGCGGAACUAGUAAAACCAAGUGUGGAAUUGUCCUUUGAUGAACAACAACAACAACAAAAGCCCUUUUACUUGUCUCCCCUCAAAGCCACUUGUCCAGAAACUGAGCACUCUUUCAUGGUCCGCACAUGGCUCAAGGAAAGCUAUUAGGUCUGAGAGCUCAAUUCAGGUCUACCUGACAUCGAUAAUAAUAUUUGGUUAGACACAAUGACUUACAUCUUUGCUUUCUGAGGUCAGGUAGUAAAAGCCACCAUCAUCGCUGCCUAUUUAAUAAUUCCUAGAGAUAGCAAUCUGGAACAAGUUAGGUGGAAUGAGACCAUGGCUUUGUCACUGAGUUUGCAAGACUCUGGGGCAGAAGGCUAGGUCAGGAAGUGAGAUGAUGACUUGCAGAAAGGGGACAAGGCCCACAUUAGGCACCUUUGCAUUCGGAGCCUAAUUCUGCUCCUUCCUAGGUGGGGCAAUCUUAGAGAAGUCACUUCACCUCUCUGUGCCUACUUUGCAAGGUUAAGUGAACUUACGGUUGCAAAACAUUUUCAACUCCAUAAAUCCAGACUUUACCACCUCUUUCUGAUUCCACGUCCCUGCUCCCACUGCACACACACACGUACACACCCUUAUGUAUGAAUCCAAUACUAUUAUCAUCAUUAUUAUUAUUACGUACUUCAUAUUACUAUUUCUAACUUUACUAAAUGUUACCUUGAGCCAGGAGCUAGGCUAAGUACUCAAUCUGCAUUAUCUUCCUUCUUUAUUGACACAGAUCCAAACAGGAAACAAUAUCUCCAUUUUAAAGAGCACAGAGAGUUCAUUCAUCAUCCCAAGGCCACCCACUUAGUAAAAUGUAUAGCCUGGAUAUCAGCCAUUCAAUGCCCACAUCAAUAUUCCCAACAACGUUAGGCAUUAACUACCAGACGAUUUUCAGUGAUACCGAGAAAGGUGUUGCGAGCUCCAUAAAUACAGCACUUUCCACUAGCAAACCCAGUGGGAUUCUUCAAUACGUAGCAAGCCUCGCCCCAGUUAACGUUCCCGUUUUGCAGAUGAGGAAAUGGAGACUUCUAGAAGAAGUCAGAGAGAUCUGAGUUUGAGUUCCUGCUUUUUCACUCACCAGCUGCACAGGUCUCUGCAAAUCACGUAAUUCCUUGGAGGUUCACCCGUCCUCACCAGCAACAUAGGGACAAUAUCUGAUCUCAAAGGGCUGGUGUGGGGUAAAUAGAAGGACAGAGCUUGGCUCCUCUUUCUAGAGGCAAUAAAGGAUCAUCUUUUCUUCUGUUCCUAGCAUGAAUGAAGAACGGUUCAUGAUUACUGUCCCAACCUCUUUCUCCACUUUGGACGCUCUUCCCUGCAUCAAAUGCACGAGGGUCCUCAAUAAUCUCACAGCGUUCUGAGUCUUAGUCCCUGACUGCUCACCAUGCAUGACCCCUUGUGGAUUCUACUUCCCAAUCUGUUCCCAGCCCCCAGCAUCUGACCUCGUUUUUGGUUUUCUAAUUAUGGCUUCGUCUUUGUGACCUCUUGGGGACAACAUUCUGGACCACGCAUGUAACCUUGGCCACCAUGCUGACUCUCCUGGAUGGGCUGCCAUCAGGGAUCAUAGGUCUCAUGAGCAGACUGUCACCGGAUGCCUCCAGAUAGGACAGAAGAAGAAAUAAAAACACUGAAACCUAAGAGUCUUGUUUCACAUUUGACCCCUUCUGUUUUGCUCCUGUUCUCAUCUCUGCCAAGGGAGGUCCACUCUUAGCCAUGGAUCAACUCUCAGCUUUUGACCAUCUUUUUUUUUUAAACUCAAGAACUGGGAAAAAAUAGCUAUAUUACCAUCAUCUUCAAAUAGAUGGGAUGUCUCAUGGAAACCAAUCCCUCCUCGAAUCAGGCAUUCAUGUAAUGCCAUGAUGAGGAUGGUGAUGACAGUGAUGGAAAUUUACAAAGAGCUUUCUAGGUGCCAGGCGCGAGGCACCAGAGCAGCACUUUUCAAUGUGUUAUGUGUAGUUAUUCCCCACAACUUCUUCACAAGGCAAGUAUUAUUCAUCUGCACUUGACUGAGGUAUAAAGGUUAGGUAACUAGAUCAAGACUGGGCAUCCCAGUGGUGACGGUGGGUUACGGAUCCUGGGCUGCGUGACUCAGCUGCUUAACCACGGUGCUGUGCUUCCUCCCACUGCUGUGUGGCUCAGACUUAUUUUCCCCAAGAACAUCUCUGACCAUUUCAUCAUGCUGUUCCCUGAAAAAGUCACUGUUUGCCACAUGUGGGUAACAUACAUCUUUUAAAAAGUCUUGAAAUUGUAGUAAAAUAUACAAAACAUGAAAUUUACCAUUGUAACUUGUUUUCAUUUUUUAGAGACAGGAUCUUGCUCUGUUGUCCAGGCUGGAGCACAGUGGUGCAGACCUCCUGGGCUCAAGCGAUCCUUCUUUCUUAGCCUCCUGAGGAACUGGGACUACAGGUGUGCAUCAUCACACCUAGCUAAUUAUUUUUGGUUUUUUUGUCUGUUUUUACUUUUUUUUUUUUUACUUUUUUGUUUUGCUUUGUUGCCAAGGCUGGUCUUCAAUUCCGGGGCUCAAGCAAUCCUCCUACCUCAGCCUCCCAAAGCACUGGGAUCACAGGCACGAGCCACUGCACCCACCUUAACCACUUUAAAGUGUGCGAUUUAGUGGCCCUUGGUACACACACAAUGGUGUGCAACCAUCACCACUGACUCCAGAACUUUAUAAUCACUGCCCCACCAAAAAAAAAGUACCCAUUAAACAGUCAGUCCCCAUUCUCCCUCUGACCUCAGCCCCGGCAACCACCAUUUCACUUUCUGUCUCUGCAAGUUUGAGGAUUCUAGGUACCUCAUAGAAGUAGAAUCGUACACGAUGUGGUCUUUUGUGUCUGGCUUCAUCACUCAGCACAGUGUCCUCAAGGUUCAGCCACAUUGUGGCCUGUGACAGUGCUUCACUCCUUUUCAUGGCUGAGCAAUACUCCAUUGCAUGGAUAGACUGCAUUUUUUAAUCCAAUCAUCCACUGAUUGAAUUUUGGGUUGAUUCUACCUUUCGGCUGAGGACACACUCUUCUUUUGGUCCACAUUCAAAGCCAUCUAAACCCCAGUUCUGAGACACCAUCCUGUCCAUGCCCCACACCCACCUCCAAACCCCACUUCUAUGCAGCUUGAGCCUCAGUGAAACCCAAGACAUCCUGAUCUGAAAAAACAAAUUGAAAAAUGGUAUCCUGCAGCUCAAGAGCACGUUCUGGGUACCAGGCAUGGUUGUUAAGUGCUUGACUCAUGACAGUCCCCAAGUCAUCGUCCUUGUUUUACAACUGAAAACACUGUGGUAAGAGAGGGAGAGUCGCUUGCUCAUGGUCACACAGCCAGUCAGGUGCAGAGAAUAACUUAAGCCCAGUCUGGAUCCCAAACGGUGCUAUUAAACAAUGCAAACUCAAAAGUGUUCAAAGCGGCUCAGACUAACGAGGUCCCUGCCUCAUCCCUACACUGGAAGUAUUAUCAUUAUAAUUGUAUGUUGUAUAUAUUGUAAGGAAGAUAAAAUUAUGCUAAGAAAGGGAAAGAGGAACUGGCAGAGAGUGUGCACUGUGGGCGCCGGUCCUGACUGCACCACUUUCUAGUUCCGUGGGCUUCGGACCCUCGCCUCCUGAAGGGCUCAGGCCCCUGGUCGGUACAAUGCACAUAAUAGUUCCAGCCUCAUAUGGUUGUGAGGAGUAAACAGGAUCAUGCACUUGGCAGGAUGAUUCCCAAUUGGGGAGAUUUCGCCCCUCAGGGGACACCUGGCAAUGCCUAGAGAUAUUUUUGGUUGUGAGGACUCAGGGAGGUGGUAGGGGAGGCUAACGGCAUCUAAUGGGGGGAGUCUCGAGAUGUUGCUACACAUCCUACAAUGCACAGGACACCCCACCCCCACAACAAAAAAACUAUCCAGCCCCAAAUGUCACUCGUCUGGAGGUUGAGAAACCCCCCGCUGAAUAAAAUGUCUGGCACGGGAUAAGAGCUCAGCAAGGGUCUGUGAGGACCACCUCAUUUACCUUUGUUCUGAACACUCCCAUGUCUGCAGGAGGCCCCUCUGCCUUGCUCCUUUCGCUCCUUUUCCCAGGCCCUUCUCCAGCCUCCGUCCUCAUGCUGCACUGACAGCACUUUGCAAACUGAAAGCAGACCCAGCAGGAAAAUCCCAAACACCUGCCUAAGGGCCCACCAGGUGCCAAGCAGACCCAGCCCUGCUCCAGUAACGAGCAAAAGCCAAACCCAGCAGGAAAAUCCCAAACACCUGCCUAAGGGCCCACCAGGUGCCAAGCUCUGUACUGGGCGAUUCACGUGGGCUCUUUCUCCCGGACCCUCACAUUAACCCAGGAUGCAAGUGGUUCGGUGGAGACAGCCUGAGUUUUAAGGCAAAGAGGCCUGGGUGGGAACUCUACUCCCAUCAUCUAUAAUGUGGGCGUAACUUACCCAAACUCCCUUAGAUUCUAUUUUCCUACCUGAUUAAUGGAGAUAAUAUUUUUUGCUUGUUUGAGAAUUCAGUGACAUAAGGCAGGGAUCAAUCAGCAUUUUUUUUUCUGUUUUCUGUAAAGCGCUAAAUAGUAAACAUCUUAGGCUUUCAGGGCCAGGUGGUCUCUGCUGCCACUCACUACUCAAUGCUGCCUUUGUGGCCUGAAAGCAGCCACAGACAACACACAGUGAAUGGGCAUGGCUGUGUGCCAAUAAAACUUUAUUUACAAAAGCAGUAGACAACACAUUGUGAAUGGGCAUGGCUCUGUUCCAAUAAAACUUCAUCUACAAAAGCAAGUGUCAGGAUGUCCACCCACCGAUGAAUGGGUAAAUAAAAUGUGUCUAUUCAUACAAUGGAAUGUUAUUCAGCCACAAAGAAAGUGCUGACACAGGACACAACAUAAACGCGCCUUGAAAACACAGUGCUCAGUCAAAGAAGCCAGACACAAAAGCACAUAGGGUAUGACUCUGUCUCUACGACAUGUCCACAGCAGGCAAGUCCACAGAUAGGGAAAGCAGCUUAGUGGUUGCCUAGGACCGCGGGAGAGGGGGGUGAGCCCAGAGAGAUGGGGAGUGACUGCUCAGGGGCACCAGGUUUGGAGGCAAUGGCCAACGGGUACACGGUUUCUUUUUCAGGUGAUGAAAACGUUCUAAAAUUGUUUGUGGUGAUGGAUGCACAGCUUUGUGAAUGUCCUAAAAACUACUGUCUUGUACACUUGAUGGGUGAGUCAUAAGUUAUGUGAAUUAUAUUAAUAUACCAGUCAAGUUGUUAUUAAAAAACAAAGUUCAGAAAACAACAACGGGUGGUGGGAUGGAAUGUGCCACCCCUGGAUGAGUAUGUAGGUGCCUACAUUAGAGUGACACAAAAUACAUGGAAAAAAGGCCUGGCAUGGUAGCUCACACCUGUAAUCCCAGCACUUUGGGAGGCUGAUGCGGGCGGAUCACCUCAGGUCAGGAGUUCUAGACCAGCCUGGCCAACGUGGUGAAACCUCCGUUUCUACUAAAAAUACAAAAAUUAGCCGGGUGUGGUUGCGGGUGCCUGUGCUCCCAGCUACUCAGGAGGCUGAGGCAGGAGAAUCGCUUGAACCCGGGAGGCAGAAGUUGCAGUGAGCCGAGAUCGUCCCACUGCACCCCAGUCUGGGCAACAGAGCAAGACUCCGUCUAAAAAACAAAAAACAAAACAAAACAAAAACAAACAGAAGAGAUGGGAAUGGCGUGGCGGCUUCCUUCCCAGCCUAACCUUGCUGCGGUGCAAAUCCUGCAAGUCACUGCACGUCCCUCCAACCCACACGAAGCAGCCUCUGACUGUUCUGCGCUGUUCACUGUGGCAUGUCCUGACUACUCAGCACGACCCACCCAGGGCUCCGCUCUCCUGUGCUCCCAUCGCUCUGUCUUCUGAUGUUGUGAUUUUUCCCUACAUGUGGCCUCCUCUUCCACGGCUCCUGGGAACUCCAUACUCUGGGCCUGUCUGCUCCCCUGACCUGUCUUGCUUCCUGGACCCCAUCUCCUUCUGGAUGGACAUCAUCAGAGAUCCUAGGUGACACCUCACUCCAUGCCUGCCCCGGGACUCUGUAGGAAGCUGGUUUGGGAGGAAUGCUUUUUAGGGCUGGGCAGGGUGGUGGAAAGCUGAAAGAUGGAUCUGACAAGCUCACACCCUCACGUCAACUCACAGUCUAGUGGAGGUGGGGAGAUGGAAAAGUAACAGGCAGUUAAACUACAACAGGAAUCUGUGUGGCACAGGGGGGAGGUGGCAGUGGGGACAGUGUGCAAGAGGACGAUGCGGGCAAUCCAGCAGGGCUUCUCGGAGGAGGAGUGGCUUGGGGCGAGCCUGCUGGACCUGCUGGUCUGGAAGUGUUUAUCAUGCUGUCCCUUCUGACUCGCGUUGUAUGCCCCUGUCCUCCUUAGGCUUGCUGAGCCUCCAAGUACUGCAUGGUAAGUCUGGUGACUGCUAUUUCGUGUUCACUCCUGUGCACAGAAAUAUACAGGUACUGGUUUUUUCUAUGGUGGGGGGUCCCUUAAAUAUCAUCAGACCCUACACUCUUUAUCCGUAUCAUCAUCUGCAUCAUAAAUGUUUAACAUGUUUUUAUUUGUCCAACAGAUAUUAACUGAUGUUAGCUCUCCUGUACCAAAUGUUAUUCUAGGUGUUAGAGAUGCAGCAGAGGAUAAAACAGACAGAAGUCUGUGACCAAGUGAAACUUGUAUUCCAAUCAGAGGAGAAAAAACAAAGAGCAGUAGUUAUAGGUCUGCUGAAGGCUAUUAUGUCCUAUGGAGACAAUAGAGUAAUGGGGAUGGAAACGCAGUGCGGGAAACUUAAGUUUUUUGGCUGGGCAUGGUGGCUCAUGCCUGUAAUCCCAGCACUUUGGGAGGCCGACGUGGGUGGAUCACCUGAGGUCAGAAGUUCGAGACCAGCCUGGCCAACAUGGUGAAACUCCGUCUCUACUAAAAUACAAACAAUUAUUUUGAAACAAAUUUUGUAAACAUAGAAAAAAUUAGCUGGGCAUGGUGGUGUGCACCUGUAAUCCUAGCUACUCGGGAGGUUGAGGCAGGAAAAUCACUUGAACCUGGGAAGCAGUGGUUGCAGUGAGCCGAGAUCAUGCCAUUGCACUCCAGCCUGGGUGACAAGAGCAAAACUCUGUCUCAAAAAAAAAAAGUUUUUAAAGGGCGAUCAGGGAACAUGACAUGUGAGCAAAGGCUUGAAGAAGAAGGGCAGGUGAGCCAGAGAUAACUGGGGGAAAGGCAUUCCAGGAAGAGAGAACAGUAUAUGCAAAGGCCCUGAGGCAGCUGAGUCCCUGGGAUCCAGGGACACAGGGAGACUAACUUUAUUCUCUUCUCUCCUCAUUCGAGGCACCUGGAAGCACUAUUUAGAGUUUGGUCUCCACCCACUUCAUAAUUCACCUGAUGGUUUCUUUUCUUUUCCUUUCUUUUCUCCUCCUCUUCCUCUUCCUCCCUCCCUCUCUCCCUCCCUUUCUUCCUUUCCUCUUCCUCUUCCUCCCUCCCUCUCUCCCUCCCUUUCUUCCUUUCCUCUUCCUCCUUCUCUUCCUGCUUCUUUUUCUCCUCCAUCUCUUCAUUUUUAGAAGAAACAAGUGGCUGCAAGGAGGAAGGUAAGUGCUUGGGGUCGUACCAUUCCUCAUCUAUAAGACAGUGUGUCCCUUCUGUCUGGGCUAUGAUAAAGCCUUAGAAGAGAAGAUUUCAGGUAAUCAAGGCCCUGCAGGGGCUUUGGUACCUGAGAGGCUGCCUUCCUGAAGGGCAUCCAAAGUCUGCAAGCCACUGCCCCUUUCACACUGCUCAUGGGCAUCGAGGAGACCCAACAUACUGAGAUGUGAGUGGGAGACAUUUCUAUCCCAGCUGCUGCUUCUGUGGACUGUGAGUCCUCUCUUCCCGACAUGGAAAUUACCAAGCUAAGUCCUGGGUGAUAGGACUGAGGGCCGGAAAACCAGAAAAUAGCAGCAAGCCACCAAGUGAUCCAGAUGGUGGAGAUGAGCGUUUUAAAGUAGGCAGAGCCGGGCAUGGUGGCAGCACCUGUGGUCCCAGCUACCCGGGAGGCUGAGGCAGGAGGAUUAUUUGAGCUGGGGAGGUGGAGGCUGCAGUGAGCCGUGAUUGUGCCACCGCAUCCGGCCUGGGUAACUGAGCAAGUCUCAAAAAAAAAAAAAAAAGCCAGAACAACACUAAUGGUUGGUUCUUUUGAAAAGCGUAAUACAAAUUUAAUCCUCUAGCAUUACUGACAAGAAAAAAUAGAGGAGAAACAAACUGCCAAUAUUUGGAAGGAAGAAGAGAGUAUCAUAGCAGAUCUUGCAGGUAACAAAAUAACAAUAAGGUGAUCAUUGGAGAAACUUUAUGCCAAUAAAAUUGAAAGUUUAGAUAAAACGGACAAAAUCCCAAAAAAACACAAAUUACCAAAAACAAAUGAAAUGAUAUAAAAAAUCUGGGCUGGGCGCGGUGGCUCACAUCUGUAAUCCCAGCAUUCUGGGAGGCCGAGGCAGGCGGAUCACAAGGUCAGGAGAUUGAGACCAUCCCACCCAACAUGAUGAAACCCCGUCUGGUGAAACCCCGUCUCUACUAAAAAUACAAAAAAAUUAGCCAGGCGUGGUGGCGGGUGCCUGUAGUCCCAGCUACUCGGGAGGCUGAGGCAGGAGAAUCACUUGAACCUGGGAGGCGGAAGCUGCAGUGAGCUGAGAUCGUGCCACUGUACUCCAGACUGGCAACAGAGCAAGACUCCAUCUCAAAAAAAAAAAAAAAAUCUGAAUAAUCCUCUAUCUAUUAAAGAAAUGCCACCUGUAAUUAAAUAGCCUUACCACACACAAAAAAGUCUUUCAGGAUCAAGUUAGCUUUAAUAGUGAAUUAAAAGGAAGAAAUCACAUUGAUCUUACAGGAAAUCUUCCAGAAAAUUAAAAACAGUCAUUUCCCAACUCGGUUUUAGGACAGAAUAACCUUGAUAAAAGAUCUGACAAAUACGACAAAGGAAAAUUUCAGGCCAAUCUUCCUCAUAAAUAUAGAUGGAAAAUCCUAGACUAAAUAUUAGCAAGUGCAAUUUGGCAAUACAUGUUAAACAAUCAUGACUAAAUUCACUUUAUUCCAGCAAUGCGACAAUGGUUUAAUAGGUAAAAACAAAUAUAUGGUAUUCCCACCUUAUUAACAUAAAAGAAAACAAGCACAUUAUCAUUUCAGUAGAUACAGAAAAAGAAUAUGGUAAGAUUUUACAGCUUACAUUAUUUUUUUUUUGAGACACGGUCUAGCUUUGUUGCCCAGGCUGGAGUGCAGUGGUAUGAUCACGGCUCACCACAGCCCUAAACUCCUAGGCUCAAGUGAUCCUCCCCUCUACAGCCUCUGAGUAGCUGGGACCACAGGCACGAGACACCACACCCAGCUAAUUUAUUAAAUUUUUUGUAGAGUUUGGGUCUCCCUAUGUUGCCCAGGCUGGUCUCAAAUUCCUGGGCCCAAGUGAGCCUCCCGCCUCAGAUUCCCAAAGUGCUGGAAUUACAGACAUAAGCCACCAUGCCCAGCCUUGUUCAUGAUUAAAAAAAAAAAAAAUCUCAGCUAGCUAGGAGUAGAGAGAACAGCUUAAUAUAAUAAGGAAUAGCCACCAAAAACUUACAAAGAACAAGCUGUUUAAGGUAAAACACAGUUGUCCCUCAGUAUCCUCAGGGGUUGGGUCCAGGACCUCCCCGCAGAUAGCAAAAUUCCUUGAUGUUCAAGUCCGUGAUAUAAAUAGCAUAAUGCUUGCAUUUAACCUAUGAACAGCCUCCUGCACACUUUAAAUCAUCUCUAGAUUACUUAUAAUACAAUGUAAAUGCUCCUUAGUUAUUGUACUGUUAUAUUUUUGUAUUGUUUUUAUUGUUGUAUUGCUAUUUUUAUUGGGAUUUUAAAAAGUAUUUUUGACCAGUUUUUGGCUGGGUCCUCAGAUGCAGAGUCCAGCGACACAGAGGGCUGAGGGUGUAGAACAUGUUCCCUCUGAGAUCACAGAUGAGACGUUCUUGCUAUCACCACUUGCAUUUCACAUUGGACUGAACGUUCUAUCCAGUGCAAAUCCUAGCCAGGCAAGAGAAAGGUAAUAAUAGGCAAAAGGAUUGUGAAGAAAGAAAGAUGAGCCUCAUUUUUUAUAGAUGUGAUUGUGUACCUUUGAUUGGGAGGGUAUAUCUGAGAGGCUUGGGAUAUGCUGGUGUUGGUGAAAUAUAAUUAAAAACAAAAUAUCCUCCAAACCCAGAGCUCUUCUCCACCCAGGUAGAAGAGAAAGAAAAUAGUUUUAUUAAUGGGUAAGCAUUAAACCAGAACAUGAUAUGCGAAGAGACUGCAAAGACAGAAAAAAAAAAUUUCACCCUUUUAUAUAGCCAAGCAGAUACAACUUAUUACAUACCUGCUCUCAAGAUAAACAACAGCUAGUCCUCAAGUUAAAGAACUUGACAGCUCUAUUUGCUGUACAUGGUUCACCGUAAAUUCACUUGGUUAUUGGGAUAGCCAACUGUGUUUGUUAAUUGGCUUAAUCCAAGGGAAAAAUAAACUUCUAGUAUCUUUAUCACAGGAGGUAGAUUUGCUACUUGGGGUGAGGUGCCCACCAAAGUUAGGCUCCAUCCCCUCCCAACAAGAAGCUGGGGAAGAUGUUUCGAGGUCCUUGAAAACACCCUCCUGGGUCAUAAUGCUGGCCGCAGGCUUACUUAGCUUUGAAAAAGAUUAGUGUAAACGUUGAAGAGAGAGAGACUUGCAAUGGCAAAAUUUUCUAAAGUAAAUGCUCUAAGCAAAGGGGACAAGGAGUAAUCGCUUCCUGAAUUUUCAACAGGGAGAAUUCAUUUUUUUUCGUUUUCGAUUUGCAUUUGCCUGUACACUGGUAAUGUUUUAUUUUUUGAUUGGAAACCUGUUUAGACAGACAGGUUUACGUGUAAAAAAAAAAUGAGAUUUUCUGAAUGUAAUACUUUUAAAAUAAAAAGACAAGGGAAAAAUGUUACACAGGCGAAAGAAACACUCUUGCACCUCAUGAGGUUUGACAUAAGAAAGCGACACGGUCGGAUCUGGUGCUAGAAAGAUCCUGCUGGCACUCAUGUGGGAGAUGGAUGAGAAAGAGAAAGGAUGGCGUAGUGGGCAGAGGCAGCCAUCAAGAGCAGAGCCUGAAGCCUGGGGAUGGGGGAGAGGUGGUGGUUUUGUUACCAGAAAGGGGUCCCGAUCAAGACCCCCAGAGAGGGUUCUUGAAUCUCGUGCAAGAAAGAAUUUGAGGCAAGUCCAUAAAGUGAAAGCAAGUUUAUUAAGAAAGUAAAGGAAUAAAAGACUGGCUACUCCAUAGGCAGAGCAGCAGCAAGGACUGCUGGACUGAGUCUCCUUAUAGUUAUUUCCUGAAUAUAUGAUAAACAAGGGGUGGAUUAUUUAUGAGUUUUCCAGGGAAGGAGUGGAGAUUUCCUGGAGCUGAGGGUGCCUCCCCUUUUUAGGCCAGUAGGGGAACUUCCUGAAGUUGCCAUGCCAUCUGUGAACUGUCAUGGUACUGGUGGGCGUGUCUCUUAGCCUGCUAAUGCAUUAUAAUUAGUAUAUAAUGAGCAGUGAGGACCACCAGAGGUCACUUGAAUCGCUAUCUUGGUUUCGGUGGGUUUUGGCAGCUUCUUUACCGCAACCUGUUUUAUCAGCAGGGUCUUUGCGACUUGUAUCUUGUGCCAACCUCCUAUUGUCAUCCUGUGACUAAGAAUGCCUUAACCUACUGGGAAUGUAGCCCAGUAGGGCUCAGCCUCAUUUUACCCAGCCCCUAUUCAAGACGGAGUCACUCUGGUUCAAACCCCUCUGACAGUUUGGUGAGAAAUCUGGGCAAGACAGGGUCAGAUUUGGUGAUGUCUUGGAUGUGAGGUGGGAGAGCCAAAAGGCAUUCCUGACUGUUUGUCUGGAGUAUGGUGGUAACCAAGAAGGGGGAAGCUGGCAGUGAUGGUGGGUGUGGACCAAAAUUUCAAUUCAGGAGGCAGGCAGAGAUGUGAGUUUGGAGAUCAGAAUGGAGAGACAGCAGUGACAGGAAGCUCUAAGGCAGGAAGGGAAGGCCAUCAGCAUCAAUCAUCUCCACGGUUCUCUCCAGUUAAACCCUUCUCAGGCACCACCCCAUCCAGGAAACCACUCCCCAAGAGGAAGAACACGUGGAACUUCCUGAAAUGCGCCUACAUGGUGAUGACCUACCUCUUCGUAUCCUACAACAAAGGGGACUGGGUAAGAAGAAGGCAGCACGGAGGGGAGGAGUGUGAGGAGAGGAAGGAAAGAGGAGGGAAGUGGGGGCACAGAGGAAGCGAAGGAGGGUGCCUCAGAGGUGCCAAGCAGGAAGUGGUGGGAGAGCCCUUCUGUAAAACACUCUCUUCUUCCCACUCUCCCACCCGCCUCCAUCUCUCAUUUCAUUCUUCCUUCCUCUCUCCUUCUUCCCUCUUUUCUCCCUCCCUCCCUCCCCUUCCUCCUUCCCUUUCCUCUUCCUUUUUUCUUCCCUCCCUUACUUCCUCCUUCUCUCUCCUCCCUCCCUAUUCUUUCCUCCUCCCUUCAUCCCUCCCUUUCUCCCUUCCUUCCUUUCUUCCUCUCUCCGUCUGCUUCCUCCCUCCCUUCUUCCUUCCCAUCCUUCUUCCCUCUCUGCCCUUCUUUCCUUCCUCCCUCCCUCCCUCUUCUUCCUCCCCGUUCCUCCCUCCCUCCCCCCUUCCUUUUCUUCCUCCCCCUUUUCUUCCUCUCCCUCUUCUUCCUCUCCCUCUUCCUCCCUCCCUCCUCCUCCCUUCCUUUUCUUCCCCCCCUCCCUGUUCUUUCCUUCCUCCUUCCCUCCUUCUCUCUCCUUCCUUCUCUUUCCUUCUUCCCUCCCUCCCACCUCUAGACUGGGAUAAAACUUCUCCCUUCUGCACUAACACAGCCCCAGGGGCUCCUUUGAAAUACUGUCACUCAUUCUGCCUCUCUCUCUGCCGCUGUCUCUUGUUCUUUCUAAGGGACGUUCAUAAGGACCAAGCCUGUUGCUGGUUGCUGGGGACUCUGAUGGUUGAGCUACCUUCAAGAAGGUCCUAAUUCUGUAAGGGAGGCAGACAUCCACAGAGAGAACCAGAUCACCGAGUGGUAGCACUUCAUGAGCAGGUGCUAGUGCAGGAGGCAGUGGCGCUUAUCUCAGCCUAGGGGAAGUGUGGGCUCAUGGAAGCCUUUCUGCAGGAGGUGACACCUCUGCUGUGGGUUAAGGACAGAAUGGAAUUAGCCAAUUGAGGAGGGGAAGCAGGGGAAGCAUUCCAGAGAAACACCAUGUGCGAGACUCAGAGAGGUGAAAAUAAGGCAGGGUGCAAGAAACUACAAGCCAGGCCGGGCACGGUGGCUCACGCUUGUCAUCGCAGCACUGUGGGAGGCUGAGGCGGCUGGAUCACGAGGUCAGGAGUUCAAGACCAGCCUGGUCAACAUGGUGAAACCCCGUCUCUACUAAAAAUACAAAAAAUAGCCGGGCAUGGUGGCGCAUGCCUGUAAUCCCAGCUGCUCGGGAGGCUGAGGCAGGAGAAUCACUUGAACCUGGGAAGCAGAGGUUGCAGUGAGCCAAGAUCACACCAGCCUGGGUGACAGAGUGAGACUCUGUCUCAAAAAAUUAAAGUAAAUAGAAAAAAAAAGAAGGAAAGGAAGGAAAGGAGGGAGGGAGGGAGGGAGGCAAGACGGAAGGGAAGGAGGGAUGGAAGGAAGGACAAGUCAUCCUUCAUUCAUUGAUUCAGUCAGUCUUCAAAUAUUCACGUGUGUAGAGGACCCAUCCUAGAUGCUGGGGACUCAGAGAAGAACGGAACCCAUAAGGUCCUUGAGUCCCCAGGGCUCCCAUGUUUGGGAUAGCAGGAGGACUGCAGAGAAACAAGCAGCCAGCUCCAAAAAACAUGAACUAAAUCAGGGUGAUAUCACAGAGUGAGCAGCCAUGGCCACGGGCAGCCUUCCCCGGGCAGGUAACGUCUGGACAUAAGAGAUGAGACAGUGGAAGGAUCUUGCCUUCAGAGCAGCUUGGGGGCAACCACUGCAAGCAAAGCAGGCAUGCACAGCAGACCCUGAGGCAGGAACACACUGAGUACCUUCGAGGAACCAAAGGAACAUCUAUGUGACCUGAGAGGGGCAGGGGGGUCCAGGUCAUGUAAGGUUCUCAUAGACCACGAGAAGGAAGCUUGUGUUCUAAGCUAGUGGACAGCCGCCAGCAAGAUCCCUUCUGAGUUAUCAAAGGAUCCUUCUCAAUGCUGCCUGUGGAGAGUGGAUCGGAAUCAGGGCGAGAGUGGGAGCAGACAGACUGAGAGGAGGAGACACACUGAGAGGAGGCCCGACCAGCCAGCGCAGGGGACCUGGCGGUGCUCAUGGAGAUGAGAGCCGUGCAGCAGUUCUAAAGGAACUGCUUAUGCGCUGGGUGUGAGGAAUAAGGAAAAUGGAGAGACCAGGGAGAUGAGCCUGAGACAGUGACUUCAGUUAUGCUAGUGGUUCUGAAACGGGGGUGACGUUGCCACCCAGGAGACACUCAGCAGUGUCUGGACCACAGGAUUGGUUGUGACAGCUGGAGGAGGGAGCUCGACUGGCAUCCAGUGGGCAGAGGCCAGGGAGGCCACUCAACCUGCCAUACGGCCCAGGACAACACGCCACGACAAAAAUAACCCAGGUCAAAACGUCAGGAACCUGAGGCUGAGAAACCCCAGCUUAGGGGAUUGUGCUGCUUAUGGGGAUGAGGAGAACUGGCUGGAAGAUGGGGAAGAAGGUGGGAGUGGUGAGAGGCGGGCUGAAUAGAGAAGCAAGACCAGAAGAUGUUACAACCAGAGGGAAAGAGCAGAGGGGGAGGACGGGAAAGAAGCGAGAGGGGGAUGGGGAGAAAGGGAGGUAAGGAAGGAAUUCACUCGCCUCACCCCAACUGUUUCUUUCUCUGUUCCCAGUUCACUUUUUCCUCCCAAGUGUUACUGCCACUACUGUAACUUGGAACUGGACAUCAGGUAUGCUAUGGCAGGGAAGUGGGCUUUUCCCACCGCUGGGGUGGGGUUAGGGGAGGUUCAUCCCAACUGCCUGGCAUUUGAGGUAAGGAACACAGGUGGAUUUGGAAGCUGCAAUCAUAGAAACCCAGAAUUCCAUGAGAAGUCCCAAGUUCGUCACCCUUACUUGCAAGCCACUGCCUGACAGGGGCAAGGAAACACAUUGUAAAUGACAGGGAUGUGCCGGGCAGGAGGAACUCCUUUAUAAAUUCACUCUAUAAUUUUUUCACAAGUCUUAGGACUUGUGGCCCAACACACACGACAUAAAAUUAACCAUUAGUGACAUUCAGUACACUCAAAAUAUUGUGUGGCCAUCACCACUAAUCUGUUUCCAGAAUCUUCUCAUCAUCCUAAAAGGGAACUCUGUACCAAGACAUCGUCUCUUCCCCCUGUUCCUGGCAACCACUAGUCUACUCUCUGUCUCUGAGAACUCACCUACUCUGGUCAUUUCAUACACAUGGAAUCAUACACUACGUGGCCCUUUGCAUCUGGGUUUAUUCAUUUGGCAUAAUAUUUCCAAGGUUCAUCAUGGUAUACCUUGUAUCAGGACUGUAUUCGUUUCUGCUGGAUAACACUCCACGGCAUGGACAUAGCACACUUUGUUUAUCCAUCAUCAGGUAAAGUGCACUGGGUUGCUCCCACCUUUUGACUGUUGUGAGUCGUGGUGCUAUGAACAAGUUAUGUUAGAAUAUCUGUUUUAAAAUCUUUUGGGGUACAAACUAGGAGUGGAAUUGCUAGGUCAUAUGAUAAUUCUGUGUUUAUAACGACCCACUGAUGCAUCCUGGAUGCAGUAGUGAACGGGGCAGACAAGAUUCCUGAGCUCACAAGAAAACAAUUAGAUGAUUACAGGUGAUACUUAGAGCUAGAGGAAAAGCUGAGGAUAUGAUGAAAAAGAGAACUAAAGAACCUUGCCCUGGAUAGUUGGGUGAUGAAGGAAAGCCUCUUUAGGAAAGUGACAAUGAAUCAAAGGCCUGUAGAAUGAGGGGUUGUCAGAUACACAGAAAACAAGUGAAAGAGCCUCCAGGUGAAGGAACUGGCUUGUACGAAGGCCCUGGGGUGGAAAGUGGCCUAGAUGUGCCUGGAGUCAGAAAGAAAAAUGGGGGCAGGAGAAGGGGGAGGGAGUGGGAGGGCACUAUGGGAGGAGUGUGGGUGACAUGCUCAGCAGACCACCUCAGACCUGGAAGAUUAGAGCAAGCAUUUUAGACCCAACCUUCAGAGCCAUGGGAAGCCACGGAAAGGCUGUCAGUGAGAAAGAGACACGUCCCAGUGACAUGAAGUGUAGAGGCCAGUUAAGAGGCUACUCAGUUUCCACGAGAUGACGGUAGCCUGGUCAAGGCUAGGGUCCAGGGUACGGAGAGAAAGUACGAAAGACAGAUGGGAGGUUUCUCUUCCCUCGAUAGCUGCAAAGAGGGUCCCCCUGGCCUCUCCCGCAUCGCCAGAGAAAGUACUAAGGACAGAUGGGAGAUUUCUCUUCCCUUGAUAGCUACAAAGAGGCUCCUCCCUGGCCUCUCCCACGUCGCCAGAGAAAGUACUAAGGACAGAUGGGAGACUUCUCUUCCCUCGGUAUCUGCAAAGAGGGUCCCCCCCGGCCUCUCCCCUGUUGCCAGAGAAAGUACUAAGGACAGAUGGGAGAUUUCUCUUCCCUUGAUAGCUACAAAGAGGCUCCUCCCUGGCUUCUCCCACGUCGCCAGAGAAAGUACUAAGGACAGAUGGGAGAUUUCUCUUCCCUUGAUAGCUACAAAGAGGCUCCUCCCUGGCCUCUCCCACGUCGCCAGAGAAAGUACUAAGGACAGAUGGGAGACUUCUCUUCCCUCGGUAUCUGCAAAGAGGGUCCCCCCCGGCCUCUCCCCUGUUGCCAGAGAAAGUACUAAGGACAGAUGGGAGAUUUCUCUUCCCUUGAUAGCUACAAAGAGGCUCCUCCCUGGCUUCUCCCACGUCGCCAGAGAAAGUACUAAGGACAGAUGGGAGAUUUCUCUUCCCUUGAUAGCUACAAAGAGGCUCCUCCCUGGCCUCUCCCACGUCGCCAGAGAAAGUACUAAGGACAGAUGGGAGACUUCUCUUCCCUUGAUAGCUACAAAGAGGCUCCUCCCUGGCCUCUCCCACGUCGCCAGAGAAAGUACUAAGGACAGAUGGGAGACUUCUCUUCCCUCGGUAUCUGCAAAGAGGGUCCCCCCCGGCCUCUCCCCUGUUGCCAGAGAAAGUACUAAGGACAGAUGGGAGAUUUCUCUUCCCUUGAUAGCUACAAAGAGGCUCCUCCCUGGCCUCUCCCACGUCGCCAGAGAAAGUACUAAGGACAGAUGGGAGAUUUCUCUUCCCUUGAUAGCUACAAAGAGGCUCCUCCCUGGCCUCUCCCACGUCGCCUGCCUUUCAUCCUCUCCCUGGCAUCCCCAGUGCCCUUUUUACAUUAAAAAAUGUCAACUCGAUCAUACGAUAUACCCCCACCCCCUGCUGCAGUCCUGCUUAAAUCCACCAGUGGAAACUCACCAACUAUGAUGAGUGUCUUUCAAACUUUAAAAGAAAGAAAAUCCAAAACACUUUUCUACUGAAAUCUUACAUGGAAUCCCAAUAUAUAAAAAAUUCUAAGUUGCUUUUCAUUACCAGAGGUACUUUUCCUAAGGUUAACUGUGUGACAUUUACUUAUUAUGAAGUGAGGUGAUGAGAUUUGCAAGCACAGGGUACAGAAGGCCUCUGCUGUCUUACGUUACUCUCUUUUACCCCGUAUCUUGCAGUGUUUCCUUUUAAUUGUUCAUACGGAGAAAAAUCUGAGCCCACAGAGAUAAGUCACUGCAAAUGCCUAAUAGUUUGCCUUGUGAAGUGUACAUGCCCUUCAGGUAAUACAAUUUUUUCCCCAAGGUCUGUAUGUAAAACAUGCAACAGGUUGGUGUGGCUCUCCAGUGAAUAAAAAUUUCAGUCCAUGUGCUAUAUUUUGGGUACACACCUAUUUUAAAAAAUAGUUUAAUUUUUGAAAUGAAAAUCAAAGCAAACCUUUGUGGAAUUCCUAAAAGAUCCCAAGUUUUCAGGGAACCUGGCAGGAAGCCUCUGCCCCAUUGAUCAAGUUCAGGUCUCUGGCAUGGUACCCAAGGGUUCUCAGGCUCCAAGCUCCUCCUGCUUCUCUAAACUUUUCUCCACUUCUCUUGAUCCCCCCACCCACAUUCCAUCCCCUGUCCAUAUUAAACCUUUUUUUUUGAGACAGGGUCUCGCUCUGUCGCCAGGCUGGAGCGCAGUGGCGCAAUCUUGGCUCACUGCAACCUCCGCCUCCCGGGUUCAAGCAAUUCUCCUGCCUCAGCCUCCCAAGUAGCUGGGACUACAGGCGAGUGCCACCACGCCCAGCUAAGUUUUGUACUUUUAGUAGAGACGGGGUUUCACCAUGUUGGCCAGGAUGGUCUCGAUCUCUUGACCUUGUGAUCCGCCCGCCUCGGCCUCCCAAAGUGCUGGGAUUACAGGCGUGAGCGGUGGCUCCCAGUCUUUUUUUUUUGAGAUGGAGGCUCACUCUGUCACCCAGGCUGGAGAACAGUGGCCCAAUCUCAGCUCACUGCAACCUCUGCCUCCCAGGUUCAAACGAUUCUCCUGCCUCAGACUCCCAAGUAGCUGGGAUUACAGGCAUGCACCACCACACCUGGCUAAUUUUUGUAUUUUUAGUAGAGAUGAAGUUUCACCAUGUUGUCCAGGCUGGUCUCGAACUCCUGACCUCAGGUGACCCACCCACCUCGGCCUCCCAAAGUGCUGGGAUUACAGGCAUGAGCCACCACGCCCCCCCAUAUUAAAUCAUUUCUGAUUCCCCCCAAAACAUCACAUUUUUUUUCCCGCUCCAUUAUGCCAUUGCACACAUUGAUUCCUUGAUCUCUGUCUACCUAGAAAAGUCCUCCUCAGUCCUCAAGAUUCACCUAAGCAAUGCUUUGGUUCAGGAACCAACAGCAAUCCUUCAGAUUCCACUGGGGAGGAUGCUGAAGGAAAUGAAUGGUGUUGAACGGUUUCUCAGGCUCUCUUCAACCAUACAUUAAAGCACCGGUCAAACCAGAUAGUUAUUUUCAUAUAAAGGUGUGCUUUCAACCCAUUAGGCAAGAGGUUGGCAAACUUUCUCUGUGAAGGGCCAAAUAUUACGUGUUGGCUUUUCAGGUCAUAUGGUCUGUUGCAACUACUCUAGUCAAAGCAAUCGUAGAGAAUACACUGAUGGCUGUGACUGUACCCAACAACUGAUGAAAGGAUAAACAAAACGUAGUGCAUUCAUACAAUGGAUUAUUAUUCAGCCCCCAAAAGAGGAAUGGGGUCCUGGCACGUGCAACAACACGGCUGAACCUUGAAAACACUGUGCUGAGUGAAAGAAGCAGACACAAAAGAUCACACAGUAGAUGAUGCCAUGUAUAUGAAACAGACAGAUCUGGCAAAUUCAAAGAGACAGAAGGCCAAUUACUAGUUGUCAGGGGCUGAGGGGAGGAAGGAACAAGGGGAGUGACUGCUUUUAAUGGAUUUCUUUUUUGGGUUGAUGAAAAUGUUCCACUCUUAGAAGUGACAAUUGCACAACAUGGCGAAUGUAAUGAAGGCCACUAAAUUGUGCCCUUUCAAAAUGGUUAAAAUGGUGAAUUUUAUGUUAUGCAUUAUGUUUGCAUUUUACCUCAAUUACAAAAAGAAACUUUAUUAAAAGGGAUGCAGGCUGCAGUUGGCCCUGCGGAACACAGUUUGAGGGCCCCUGCUCACAUAGACUGUGAGCCCCUGUGGGAGCAGGAAGUACCCCUGAUCCAUCCCUGGAACUCCAGCACCCAGAAGCAAACCUUAAGGUUCUCUUCCUGCAACUCUGAGUGACUCCAGCACACCAGGCUAGGGGGUGCAGCCCAGCCAGGCCUGGGCAGUCCCUGCUCCUGCGGGGCGCGCCCUCUAGUGGGAGGUAGGGGUGCAACACAAGCUCAGGCCCGGCGCCGGGACAGUGAGGAACUGGAGGGGGCGCUGCUUCCCACUGGCUGGUUUCUAGAAGAGCCCUGCUCUGAGGAGGAGACACUUGCCCUGGUGAUGGGGCAGAGCUAGGGUCCAUAAGAUCUGAGGGAAGCGUGUUCCAGCUGCUGGAACAGCCCGGUGGGAAUAGGGACAAACUUGGUGGAACCUAGUGAGUGGGGAGAAUGGGCUAAGCUGGAGGGAGGAGGUGGGCUUGAGGCAGGUCACAAAGAGCCCUGUAGAGGUGGAUGGAGAGGGCACCAGGCAAGGAGUAUGAGAAUGCAUGAAGACGAAAAUCAAUGCACAAAUACAUUUCUCUCUCCUUUCUUAGGGAUGAUCCCUGCUGUUCUUUCUAGUGAGCCUGCUCCAUCUCAGCUUAGCCUUCACAAGGCCUCCAUCUCCCAGGCAUUCUAACCUCUGAAGAAAGCUCUCUGUCCCCUGGACUGCCUGUGUGGAGGGUAAUGAACUGGGUCCUUUAAGGAAUGGCACCUGGGUGCCCAGAGGCAUGGCCAGAAGGUGUCUGUGGGGGCCAUGCCUUAGGGGGAUGCACCCAGGGCGGCUGAGAGAGCAACUGCAGGAGUUUCCCCUAAAAUCUCUCCUCCAGAUCGUUCUCGAACUUUCCCCACUACUUCCAUAAUAAAAUGUAUACUUGUUGAAAUGGC